GUGCGAUCAGAUCGAUCUAAGAUGGCGACUGUCGAACCGGGUGCUGUGAGGAAAUGCAUGGUUUGUUGAAAAGAACUGAGGACUGACAGCCGCCUCCUCCAUGAUUACCCUGGCUCUCUGUCCCACCCUUCUCAUGGCGCUUGGGGGACCAUGGCUGAUCCUGUCCUGAGACAAAUUAAGACUCCUGUGGUGAAGCAGUUGGUCGAGAAAAAGUGAUGCAUGAAAAAGAAGCAAAACAAGAAGGAAAGAAAAAAAAUGAGAGCUGAAGAUGGUGAAAAUGAUGCCAUUAAAAAGCAGGCAGAAAGUCUGCGAGAAUCCCAGGAAACCACCCCUACUCCUAAUCCCCCGACUACAGAAGAGGAGAAAACGGAAUCUAAUCAGGAGGUUGCUAACCCAGAACACUAUAUUAAACAUCCCCUACAGAACAGAUGGGCACUCUGGUUUUUUAAAAAUGAUAAAAGCAAAACUUGGCAAGCAAACCUGCGGCUGAUCUCCAAGUUUGAUACUGUUGAAGACUUUUGGGCUCUGUACAACCAUAUCCAGUUGUCUAGUAAUUUAAUGCCUGGCUGUGACUACUCACUUUUUAAGGAUGGUAUUGAGCCUAUGUGGGAAGAUGAGAAAAACAAACGGGGAGGACGAUGGCUAAUUACAUUGAACAAACAGCAGAGACGAAGUGACCUCGAUCGCUUUUGGCUAGAGACACUUCUGUGCCUUAUUGGAGAAUCUUUUGAUGACUACAGUGAUGAUGUAUGUGGCGCUGUUGUUAAUGUUAGAGCUAAAGGUGAUAAGAUAGCAAUAUGGACUACUGAAUGUGAAAACAGAGAAGCUGUUACACAUAUAGGGAGGGUAUACAAGGAAAGGUUAGGACUUCCUCCAAAGAUAGUGAUUGGUUAUCAGUCCCACGCAGACACAGCUACUAAGAGCGGCUCCACCACUAAAAAUAGGUUUGUUGUUUAAGAAGACACCUUCUGAGUAUUCUCAUAGGAGACUGCGUCAAGCAAUCGAGAUUUGGGAGCUGAACCAAAGCCUCUUCAAAAAGCAGAGUGGACUGCAUUUAAAUUUGAUUUCCAUCUUAAUGUUACUCAGAUAUAAGAGAAGUCUCAUUCGCCUUUGUCUUGUACUUCUGUGUUCAUUUUUUUUUUUUUUUUUGGCUAGAGUUUCCACUAUCCCAAUCAAAGAAUUACAGUACACAUCCCCAGAAUCCAUAAAUGUGUUCCUGGCCCACUCUGUAAUAGUUCAGUAGAAUUACCAUUAAUUACAUACAGAUUUUACCUAUCCACAAUAGUCAGAAAACAACUUGGCAUUUCUAUACUUUACAGGAAAAAAAAUUCUGUUGUUCCAUUUUAUGCAGAAGCAUAUUUUGCUGGUUUGAAAGAUUAUGAUGCAUACAGUUUUCUAGCAAUUUUCUUUGUUUCUUUUUACAGCAUUGUCUUUGCUGUACUCUUGCUGAUGGCUGCUAGAUUUUAAUUUAUUUGUUUCCCUACUUGAUAAUAUUAGUGAUUCUGAUUUCAGUUUUUCAUUUGUUUUGCUUUUGUUUUUUUCCUCAUGUAACAUUGGUGAAGGAUCCAGGAAUAUGACACAAAGGUGGAAUAAACAUUAAUUUUGUGCAUUCUUUGGUAAUUUUUUUUGUUUUUUGUAACUACAAAGCUUUGCUACAAAUUUAUGCAUUUCAUUCAAAUCAGUGAUCUAUGUUUGUGUGAUUUCCUAAACAUAAUUGUGGAUUAUAAAAAAUGUAACAUCAUAAUUACAUUCCUAACUAGAAUUAGUAUGUCUGUUUUUGUAUCUUUAUGCUGUAUUUUAACACUUUGUAUUACUUAGGUUAUUUUGCUUUGGUUAAAAAUGGCUCAAGUAGAAAAGCAGUCCCAUUCAUAUUAAGACAGUGUACAAAACUGUAAAUAAAAUGUGUACAGUGAAUUGUCUUUUAGACAACUAGAUUUGUCCUUUUAUUUCUCCAUCUUUAUAGAAGGAAUUUGUACUUCUUAUUGCAAGGCAGUCUCUAUAUUAUGUCUUCUUUUGUGGUGUCUUCCAUGUGAACAGCAUAAGUUUGGAGCACUAGUUUGAUUAUUAUGUUUAUUACAAUUUUUAAUAAAUUGAAUAGGUAGUAUCAUAUAUAUGGAAUUAAAUUGAUGUGGCUAUCUUUGUUUUUUUAUAAAGUAAGGCACAGUCAUUCAGUCUUAGGUAAAUAAUGUACUCUCUUAAUAUGUUAAUACUCAUGAGAAUUGGGAUCUGAUGCAUCACCAUUUGAUUGGUAGCAACAGUGGUUGUAAAACUUGGUUGCUGAAUUGAGUUGUUUCUAUGUUAAGUGUCAAAAUGAUAGUGUAGGGAAAGUACAGGUGGUGGGGACAUAUGCAUUAAGAAUCUUGUUAGUGUUGCAAUCUAAAUAGAAUGGAAUAAACAGGUGUUAAGACAUAUUUAUAGUGGUAAAUUGUUGUAGUAUGGUAUUCUGUAAACUUGAAAACUUGAUCUACUCUUUGUAGGUAUCAUUUGAAAGCAAACUUGAAAAUGUUUUGUACAUAGUACAUACUUGUAUAGUCCUGUGAGAUGAAGUAUGGCUAUCAGACCAAAGGAUAAGCCAAACUGUAGGUAGCAGAAUGGAAAUUAUUAUUUUGAGAGGAAAAUUUGUCUUUGAAUGGUGAUUAUGACUUAAUCAUUUUAAAACUGAUAAACUUGACAAAAACCCUGUAUGAAAUAAACAUGAAAUUAAUAGCA